GUAAUGCGGUAGCGCGGGGAAUUUCGAGUGGUGUUGGAGCGCCGGAGGCUAGUGGGUGGCUGACCCCCAGCAUCCUCGGGAGCGACCAUGGACUCCCUGGCCGAGUCUCGGUGGCCUCCGGGCCUGGCAGUCAUGAAGACAAUAGAUGAUUUGCUGCGGUGUGGAAUUUGCUUCGAGUAUUUCAACAUUGCAAUGAUAAUACCUCAGUGUUCACAUAACUACUGCUCUCUCUGUAUAAGAAAAUUUCUGUCCUAUAAAACUCAGUGUCCAACUUGCUGUGUGACUGUCACAGAGCCGGAUCUGAAAAAUAACCGCAUAUUAGAUGAACUGGUAAAAAGCUUGAAUUUUGCACGGAAUCAUCUGCUGCAGUUUGCUUUAGAGUCACCAGCCAAAUCUCCUGCUUCUUCCUCUUCAAAGAAUCUUGCUGUCAAAGUAUAUACUCCUGUAGCCUCCAGACAGUCUUUAAAGCAGGGGAGCAGGUUAAUGGAUAAUUUCUUGAUCAGAGAAAUGAGUGGUUCUACAUCAGAGUUGUUGAUAAAAGAAAAUAAAAGCAAAUUCAGCCCUCAAAAAGAGGCGAGCCCUGCUGCAAAGACCAAAGAGACACGUUCUGUAGAAGAGAUCGCUCCAGAUCCCUCAGAGGCUAAGCGUCCUGAGCCACCCUCGACAUCCACUUUGAAACAAGUUACUAAAGUGGAUUGUCCUGUUUGCGGGGUUAACAUUCCAGAAAGUCACAUUAAUAAGCAUUUAGACAGCUGUUUAUCACGCGAAGAGAAGAAGGAAAGCCUCAGAAGUUCUGUUCACAAAAGGAAGCCGCUGCCCAAAACUGUAUAUAAUUUGCUCUCUGAUCGUGAUUUAAAGAAAAAGCUAAAAGAGCAUGGAUUAUCUAUUCAAGGAAAUAAACAACAGCUCAUUAAAAGGCACCAAGAAUUUGUACACAUGUACAAUGCCCAAUGCGAUGCUUUGCAUCCUAAAUCAGCUGCUGAAAUAGUUCGAGAAAUCGAAAAUAUAGAGAAGACUAGGAUGCGUCUUGAAGCUAGUAAACUCAAUGAAAGUGUAAUGGUUUUUACAAAGGACCAAACAGAAAAGGAAAUAGAUGAAAUCCACAGUAAAUAUCGUAAAAAACAUAAGAGUGAAUUUCAGCUUCUGGUGGAUCAGGCUAGAAAAGGAUACAAGAAAAUUGCUGGAAUGUCACAAAAAACAGUAACAAUAACAAAAGAAGAUGAAUCUACAGAAAAGCUAUCUUCUGUAUGCAUGGGACAGGAAGAUAAUAUGACCUCAGUAACAAACCACUUUUCUCAAUCAAAGCUGGACUCCCCAGAGGAAUUGGAACCUGACAGAGAAGAGGAUUCUUCUAGCUGUAUUGAUAUUCAAGAAGUUCUUUCUUCAUCAGAAUCAGAUUCAUGCAAUAGUUCCAGUUCAGACAUCAUAAGAGAUCUUUUAGAAGAAGAGGAAGCCUGGGAAGCAUCACAUAAAAACGAUCUUCAAGACACAGAAAUAAGUCCAAGACAGAAUCGCCGCACAAGAGCCGCUGAAAGUGCUGAGAUUGAACCAAGAAACAAGCGUAAUAGGAAUUAAUGUGGGCUUUUGCUGACUUUUCAAAUGCAUUGAUUAGAAUACCGUACUUUUGGUUGCCACAGAUAGAUUUUCUAUUUAUAAAUGCCCAAGGAAAGAUGCUAAAUUCUAAAUAUUACGGUUAGCUGAUAUUCAUUCUUUUCUGCUUUUCCAGAGGGGAAAAAUGUUACAAAAUAUCCUUACUUGGUCAGUUGCCUCCUGCCUCUAAAACAUCUCUCUCUAAAAAUACUGACAUUUCACACAGGUACCAGCUUUGCAGAGGAGGUAGACUCUUUGGCACUUUGGCACAGGGAUUUGGUUUGGUUUGGUUUGGUUUGAUAAUUAAAUUUCAGAAUGUCCUUAGGCCAUUCUCCUUCUCUUCCAUGGAGAAUCCAGCCUCACAAAAGGAUUCUUUCAACUUCUUUAUUGCAAGAAACAGUUGAGUUAAAUGUUUGUUUUUGGAAAGGCGGGAUGUCAGUUCACAUCCUUGGUGUGUGUAAGUACCGAUGCACGCCACCACCAUGCCUGUGUUACAGCAGCUCCAUGAUGGUUGUUGCCCGAGGUUAAUGUAGUUGUUUGUUAGACCUGUGUCUUACACAUUUCUCAGAGUAGGAUAUUAGUAUUAUAAUUUAAAGCUACGACAGUCACAAAGUCACAAUAACUUAGAAACAUUGCGCAUAUUCUUCUGAAAUAGCACUUAAAAAUGAUUAGUGUCAGUAUUUUUUCACUUGGGUCAAUCAAAUCUGUAACACUGAAUCCAAGCUAUUAAACAAAAAGUAUGCAAUGAAUGAAUUUUGUAAAUGAAUAGAGAGUAUCAGUUUACAAUAAUGUUCUUAAAACAGUAUCCUCUGGAUAGUUGAGUAUGGGUUAGAAAUCAUUGAAAUGGAUUGGUCAGAAAUUGCUAUCUGUGUAAAAUGUCUACCAGUAGCCAGAUGCUUCCAGAGUUCUUAAUGCCUCUCUGGCAUUUCAGAGCCAGCAUCCCCCAACUCCCACCCCUCUGCCAUCACCCAACCCAAACACAUCAGCUUUCAAAUGAGAUGAUAGUAAAUGCGGCAAUGUUAAGACAAGAAAUUUAUGAUUUGCCAGAUUCAACAUUUAUGACCUCCCCUUCCAAAGACUGUCUCCGUUGACCUUGUCUUUUUGGUAUGCCUUGGGGUUUCUGAUAAUGUGUGGAGUCUCAUUAUGGCUGAGAGUUUAGUGUUUUCACAGUGAAGUGCAGACAUUUGAUUUCUUUAUGAGUUCCCUGUGUUAGAAAUGGCUAUAGAAAAAUUUGUCAUAAUAAUUUCAUUUGCAUGAAAUCCUGAGGGGUGCAUUAAGGAAACUAAAAGCACCACUUACCAAAUCUAUCGGCAGAACUGAUGUGAGGUAAGUGAGCAUGUCAAACAAAAUAGGAGCUCACAUGGAUAUAUUUAUGUCACUGAGUUGUCAGAAAUUAUGUCAAAAUGAAAACUGUUUGUUUCAUGACAAAUUAUAUAGUCUAUAAAUUAAACUGGAAGUAAUUAUUACUUUAAUUGCAGCAAAAGGAGUUUGUGAGGGAGCGGUGAGACCCAAGAUUGGGAAAGUAGGCACAUGAGUUCAUUCAGCAAAUAUUUGGUUAUCUAUGUCUGUCACUGUGCUGACACUGGGAAUACAAAGGUGGCCAAAGAUCAUCUAGAACAAUGGUUCCCAGUGGGGUGGGCAGAAAGAUUUUGCCCCCCAGGAGACAGCUGGCAAUGUGUGGAGACACUUUUGGAGGUGGAGGGUGGUGAGGGGUACUACCAGUAUCAAUGGGUGGAGGCCAGGGAUGAGGCUAAACACCCAACCCUCAUGGAUUAGUUUGCCAGGGCUGCCGUCACAAGAUACUGCAGACGGGGAAGCUUACACAACAGAAAUGUGUAUUCUCAGAAUUCUGGAGGCUGGAAGUCCAAGAUCAGUAGGGUUUCUUCUUCGGCCUCUCUCCUUGGCUUCCACUCAUGGUGUCCUUGCAUGGUCUUUUCUCUGUGUGCACAUGACUGUGCAGGACUGGUGUCCCGAUUUCUUGUAGGGACAGCAGUCAUUGGAUCAGGGCCCAUGCGUAUGGCCUCAUUUUACUUCAGUUACCUCUUUUUUAGAUAGAGGGCCCUAUCUCUAAAUACUGUCACAUUCUGAGAUACCGGCAGUUAAGACUUCCAACAUAUUUAGUGGUAGGGGUUAAGGGGCACGCUUUAGACUACAACACUCCACAGUAAAGAAUUAUCCAGUCUAACAUGUCAGUUGUGCCAAGACUGAGAAACCUGUAAUGUAAAGGAACUCCCAAGUCUACCUGAAAAGUAAGGUCUAAAGAGCAUUUAUUGAGCACUAUCUGUUAGCACUUAGCAUAUGUUUAAUAUUCAUACAUUGAAAGAAAUGUAUGUUCAUAUCCAUCUGACAAAGAUUAAGGAACUUAGAGUAAGUAAUAGAUCCAAAAUUGAAACUGAUAAACUUCUGGUUCUAAAAUUCACCUUUUAGUGAAAAUACAGUUUCUCACCAAACUUACAGUAAUUCAGAGUUAUUAACUCUUUCUACCUCCUCACUCCCCUCAAAGUUAUAACAUCUCCCAUCAACAUCAGCUCAGAAUGGCAGUGAUGCUUAUGGUUUGUGGGGGUGCAGGUGAGCUGCUGGAUGCACUUUAGAUGGCCUAGUAUGCCAGGCCGUCCUUUCAUCCUCUACUCUCGUCUUUCUUUUUCGACCUCAUGUUGAGGAUUACUGGUCUAGUUGAAAAAAGAAUUCAUACACAUAAGACCAUGUAUAUAAUAGAGGGAGGUAUGCCUUUAAAAACAAAAUUACAUGGUAAAGACUGAUGUGUCAACAGGGAUAGACAACAUAGAGAAGGCUAGAACUGUUUCUGGAAAAAAACCCAAAAACAAUGGAUUUCAAACUUCUUAGCAUCCGAUAAAAGAAAGUAGCAAUUAUUCAAAUGAGAAACACUUCUGUCUGUUAUGUACAUAUUAUGAAAGUAUGAACAUAAGAGGGAAAACCACAACCAUUACAUUUUUUACCAUUUCAGUAAUUUUUUUUUGGUUUUUAGUCUGUUUUUAGACAUCCUUAAGAACAACUAUCUGAGGCUGUAAACAAGUAUUUACAUUAACACCCAUGAUACUGACUUUAUACUCCCUACCUGCAUUGAGACCUUAAAGGGGGCAUUUCUCCAUUCCUUCUGUGUAUUUCUGGGUAUCCCCAGGUUCAGAUAUUCAGAAUACAGAUACAAGUCCAUGCUUGCAUAUGUUGCUGCUCCCCCCGACAGACUUCUACCAGCAUCUGCCCUCCUCACCGCUGCUCUGUCACGUGCACUGCGGCUGGCCCUGCUGGAAAGUCCUACCUUGCCUAGGACGCCAUCCCCGAUAUAGCCCCAAGAUGCAAACCUGCCAAGUGCUAGGGCAGCCCUGCCUUCCUGUCCAUUUCAGUCUCUUGGCCUUGCUGUGUUCCAAGUGGAAAUGGGAGUGUGCUUUCCUGGUUUGCUAGUGUACUAUCACCCGGACCACAGCGUCCUGUGCAAAAAUUUGCUUCCUCUCUCUUCCCCUUUCACUCUUUCUCUUUUCUCUUCCCCACCCCCUUUUUUUUCUCUUUCCCCUUACCUUUCUUUCCUUUCCACUCUUCCUGUCCUUCCUUCCUUCAACUAUUAGGACUAUAUGUCAAGUAAUGUGCAAAACAAAGACAGUUCCUGCCCUGAUGGAGCUUGUAGAUCAGAAGGGAAGAUGAGCAUUAAGUAAUUAUAUAGAUUAAUGUACAACUGUGAUGAGUGCAACAAAAGAGAGGUUCAUGGCACUAUCAAACAUGCAAUGGACGGAUUUUGUUUUUGCCUAUAAACUCUUGCCAUAGAAAGCUUGAAAAUCAGUCCAGGGGGACAGCAUUAAUCACCAUGUUCUUUCCUUAUCCCUGUCUUCCCCAAAAUUCAUGUGUUGAAACUUAACAAGAGGUGGGAACUUUAGGAUGUGAUUAAGUCGUGAGGGCACAGCUCUUAUAGAUGGGGUCACGGUCCUUCUAAAAGGGCUUGAGGGAGUGGUUUUGUUUCCUUCCAUCCCUUCCGCCACAUGAGGACACAGUCUUCGUUCCCUCUGGAGGACUCAGCAACAACACACCAUCUUGGAAGCAGAGAGCAGUCCUCACCAGACACGGAAUCUGCCAGUGCCUUGAUCUUGGACUUACCAGCCUCCAUACCUGUGAGAAAUAAAUUUCUAUUGUCUAUAAGUUACCCAGACUGUGGUAUUUUCUUCUGGCAGCACAAAUGGACACCCAGAAACUGAUGCAUGCAUCUUCUGACUCCUUUGAUUCCAAAAUACAAAAUAUUAGAAUAAAGUUAUGGAAGUCA